AAAGUGCGGGGUCGGCCGGGUGCUGGGCCGAGGCCGAGGCCGGGGCGGGAUCCAGAGCGGGAGCCGGCGCGGGAUCUGGGACUCGGAGCGGGAUCCGGAGCGGGACCCAGGAGCCGGCGCGGGGCCAUGGCGAGGCGCGGGCCAGGGUGGCGGCCGCUUCUGCUGCUCGUGCUGCUGGCGGGCGCGGCGCAGGGCGGCCUCUACUUCCGCCGGGGACAGACCUGCUACCGGCCUCUGCGGGGGGACGGGCUGGCUCCGCUGGGGCGCAGCACAUACCCCCGGCCUCAUGAGUACCUGUCCCCAGCGGAUCUGCCCAAGAGCUGGGACUGGCGCAAUGUGGAUGGUGUCAACUAUGCCAGCAUCACCCGGAACCAGCACAUCCCCCAAUACUGCGGCUCCUGCUGGGCCCACGCCAGCACCAGCGCUAUGGCGGAUCGGAUCAACAUCAAGAGGAAGGGAGCGUGGCCCUCCACCCUCCUGUCCGUGCAGAACGUCAUCGACUGCGGUAACGCUGGCUCCUGUGAAGGGGGUAAUGACCUGUCCGUGUGGGACUACGCCCACCAGCACGGCAUCCCUGACGAGACCUGCAACAACUACCAGGCCAAGGACCAGGAGUGUGACAAGUUUAACCAAUGUGGGACAUGCAAUGAAUUCAAAGAGUGCCACGCCAUCCGGAACUACACCCUCUGGAGGGUGGGAGACUACGGCUCCCUCUCUGGGAGGGAGAAGAUGAUGGCAGAAAUCUAUGCAAAUGGUCCCAUCAGCUGUGGAAUAAUGGCAACAGAAAGACUGGCUAACUACACCGGAGGCAUCUAUGCCGAAUACCAGGACACCACAUAUAUAAACCAUGUCGUUUCUGUGGCUGGGUGGGGCAUCAGUGAUGGGACUGAGUACUGGAUUGUCCGGAAUUCAUGGGGUGAACCAUGGGGCGAGAGAGGCUGGCUGAGGAUCGUGACCAGCACCUAUAAGGAUGGGAAGGGCGCCAGAUACAACCUUGCCAUCGAGGAGCACUGUACAUUUGGGGACCCCAUCGUUUAAGGCCAUGUCACUAGAAGCGCAGUUUAAGAAAAGGCAUGGUGACCCAUGACCAGAGGGGAUCCUAUGGUUAUGUGUGCCAGGCUGGCUGGCAGGAACUGGGGUGGCUAUCAAUAUUGGAUGGCGAGGACAGCGUGGCACUGGCUGCGAGUGUUCCUGAGAGUUGAAAGUGGGAUGACUUAUGACACUUGCACAGCAUGGCUCUGCCUCACAAUGAUGCAGUCAGCCACCUGGUGAAGAAGUGACCUGCGACACAGGAAACGAUGGGACCUCAGUCUUCUUCAGCAGAGGACUUGAUAUUUUGUAUUUGGCAACUGUGGGCAAUAAUAUGGCAUUUAAGAGGUGAAAGAGUUCAGACUUAUCACCAUUCUUAUGUCACUUUAGAAUCAAGGGUGGGGGAGGGAGGGAGGGAGUUGGCAGUUUCAAAUCGCCCAAGUGAUGAAUAAAGUAUCUGGCUCUGCACGAGA